CCCCACAUCCAUCAAACCCGUGCGGUGGGCGGGACGAGCUGCAUGCACUAUCCUUCUAGGCUCUCUGGCUCUGGCGGGACUGUGGGCCAGCUCUGUCAUCCACCACCGCCCUGCGUGACUUACAUUGGAGAAACAUGUCUUCUGUCUCUUGUUACCCAUUACCCAGCGUCGGAAGCCCUAGGAUACGGGCUGUGUGCCGGACUUUUGUGGGGGCUCUUAGGGCACAGAUAAACGAGAUCCCGCCCCGCCCCUACCCUCACAGUUUCCUUAAUAAUUCCAACCAUCUCUUCAUUAUGCCCUGGUCCCAAAUAAUCUUUCUUCCCCCCACCCCUAAGCAUAGUGUUUUCAAGGUUCAUCCAUGGUUUAUGAGCAUGCAUCAAUACUUUAUUCCUUUAUGGCCCGUCAUAUAGUACAUUUGGUCUGAGUCAUUCCUGCUUCUAGUACAAGAUGCACCUGUUUGCCUUCCUUAGAAGGUUAGGGCAGAGGAAAGGGGUCCAGUCACCUUUACAGUCCUUGAUACGUAGACCAAAGUUGUGCAUAUGUUAGGCCUCAAGAAACAUUUGUCAAAUUAAGUUUAUGCUGGUGUCCCUGUGUUACAGCUGAGGGGGUUAAAGGAUGCGAUUUGCCUGAAACCCUCACACCUGAAUACUGACAGAAUAUGGACUCGGACCACCAGUCUAGUGCUUUUUUUUUAAAGAUGGAAUCUCGCUGUGUCGCCCAGGCUGGAGUGCAGUGGCCUGAUCUCGGCUCACUGCAAGCUCUGCCUCCCGGGUUCACGCCAUUCUCCUGUCUCAGCCUCCCGAAUAGCUGGGACUACAGGCGCCCACCACCACGCCCGGCUAAUUUGUUGAAUUUUUAGUAGAGACGGGGUUUCACCAUGUUAGCCAGGAUGGUCUCGAUCUCCUGACCUUAUGAUCCGCCCACCUUGGCCUCCCAAAGUGCUGGGAUUACAGGCGUGAGCCACCACACCCGGCCAGCCUAGUGCUUUUUUACAGAUGUUGCCUUGCCAGCCAGCGGGACUGACCUCCAAAAUUUAAAAAGAAAAAAAAAGUGCAGGGCAAGCCUAAGAUCAGCUACUAGGCUGACAUUAAAUAAGCAUUUUCCACUUGUCAUUAUCUUAGGGGAAUUGGGAAGCUGCCUCUAGCACUUAAAAUACAAGCCACUUCCCUCUGUCUAGGAAGUACUAAAGAAAUACAAAAGUUGACAGAAAAGGAAUGAAGUCCAGUUGGUCUCGCAAAUCCCCUGAGAUAGUCCAGCAGGGGAAGGGACUUACUCAGGGGUACACAGUGAGUUAGAAGCAGAGCUGGGACUGGAAUCAAGGUGUUUUGUCGCUGCUAGUUGAAGGCAGUUUUCGUUGCGCUGCCCUGCUGCGUGCUGUGGGAGCUGUCGUUGGAUGUUUGCACAAGUGUGGGCAUAAAACCUUCGAUGUCUGGAGUGCUUUUUAUUUUUCAGUGUGCUCUGCUGUUUACUGAGCUCCCGUGUUCUGGUAUUCAUUGACCAUCUUUAUUUACCACUACCUACCUUGUGUCAGGGGCUGUGGAAUCCAAGAUGUCUGCAACAUGCUCCCCACCGCCCACACAGUCUAGUUGGGAAGCAGUUAUGUCCACGUAUUCGUUCAUUCAGUAUUUUAUUUCUCAUUGAGAUGUAAUUCACGUGAUGUAAAGUCCUUUUAACGUAUACAAUUCAGUGGGGUUUUUUGUUGUUUAGAGACAGGGUCUGCCUCUGUCACCCAGGCUGGCGUGCAGUGGCAUGAUCUUGGCUCACUGCAACCUCCGCCUCCCAAGCUCAAGCAAUCCUUCCACUUCAGCCUCCCAAGUAGCGGGGACCAUAGGUGUGCACCAUCACGUGCAGCUAAUUUUUGUAUUUUUUGUAGAGAUGGGUUUUCGCCAUGUUGGCCAGGCCGGUCUUGAACUCCUGAGCUCAAGUGAUUCAGCCGCUGAAAGUGUUGGGAUUACAGGCCGAGACGCAUCCAGAGCUUUCGUGACCGGGGACUGUUCUGAAGCAGGCCUCGUGGAUGACGUAUCCGACCUGUCAGCCGCUGAGAUGCUGACACUUCACAAUUGGCUUUCAUUCUAUGAGAAGAAUUAUGUGUGUGUUGGGAGGGUGACAGGACGGUUCUACGGAGAGGAUGGGCUGCCCACCCCGGCACUGACCCAGGUAGAAGCUGCGAUCACCAGAGGCUUGGAGGCCAACAAACUACAGCUGCAAGAGAAGCAGACAUUCCCGCCGUGCAACGCGGAGUGGAGCUCAGCCAGGGGCAGCCGGCUCUGGUGCUCCCAGAAGAGUGGAGGUGUGAGCAGAGACUGGAUUGGCGUCCCCAGGAAGCUGUAUAAGCCAGGUGCUAAGGAGCCCCGCUGCGUGUGUGUGAGAACCACCGGCCCCCCUAGUGGCCAGAUGCCGGACAACCCUCCACACAGAAAUCGUGGGGACCUGGACCACCCAAACUUGGCAGAGUACACAGGCUGCCCACCGCUAGCCAUCACAUGCUCCUUUCCACUCUAAGCCGUAGCCUCUUCUGUUAAUAACACACAGAGAGCUCUGCCAAGCACCUGAGUAGGCCCUUGACACUUGUGUGCCCUGGGAUGCCUCCUGGCGCGAAUCAGGAGGGUCUGGAAGGACUCUGGCUAUAUUCUGCAAAUGUGGCUCAUGCCCCUUACCGUGGCUCGGCGUUGUGGUGCCUGAGGGACAGCCGGCCACCUGCCCAGUACUGGUCAGCUUUUCAACACUAUUCCCUUUGACCUACUGGCCAUCUUCCUCACAGCCCUCAGAUAUCAACGGGCACAAAUAAGACCAACUCAAUUUCCACUUGAAUUUACAACCAAAAGCCUGCUGAGUUGAUUACAGCUGGGCCAAUACAGUACGAGGCAAUAACAAAUUAGUGUGGGUUGAUUCUGGAAUUGGAAAAGCUUUUGCUUGUAUGGAUACAGCAAAUCCAGAUGUCUCUGAACAAAGCAACAAUUUAAAGCAACGACAUUUUCUGUCCUUUAAGCACUUAAAAUCAGGUGUGGUGUGUUUUCAAAGGCAGAAGUCUGCAUUUUGAGCAAAAGGUGGCUUCCCAGCUCUAACAAGGUAACUGGUUAGCAUGACAUUAAAGCUUGGGCAAGGCUUCAAACUUAAGGUG